GAUUACAGGCGUGAGCCACUGCACCUGGCUAAAACCUACAUUUUUUUCAAUUCUCUUUUUAACAUUUGAAAAUUUUGCUUAAUCUAAAAUAUACUCCAGAAGUUUAAAUGGAAAGACCUUAAUAAAAUAUUCAGUCAAAUGCUCUUCCUUUAGAAAUGGAGGUACUGAAGUUCAUUUCUCCUAUCAUUCUAAAUUGAUGUUUCAUUUUGACUAUAUAUUUAGUGAGUUAUGGCAGUAAAAGCAGCUUUAAUUUUUUUUCUGAAAGCCUACUCAUAUUGGAGCCCUUUAUAACUUGCCUCUUGAAGUAUAUAUAUUUAUUCAUACAAAUCAAACACUGAUGUCUGUGAAGUUUCAUAUCAUCUUUUAUAUUUGAAUUUUGUUCAUAUACUUAUUGUCACCCAGGCUGGAAGUACAGUGGUGUAAUCUCAGCUCACUGCAACCUCUGCCUCCUGGGUUCAAGUGAUUCUCCUGCCUCAGCCUCCCGAGUAGCUGGGAUUACAGGCAUGUGCCACCAUGCUGGCUAAUUUUUCUAUUUUUAGUAGAGAUGGGGUUUCGCCAUGUUGGCCAGGCUGGUCUGGAACUCCUGACCUCAAGUGAUCUGCCCACCUCAGCCUCCCAAAGUGCUGGGAUUACAGGCAUGAGCCACCAAGUUUUUAAUUGAUGGCAUUUUAAAGAAUACCUCAUAUUUUAUACUUUCCAGACAUUUUCCCCACUUAUAUGAAAUUUAAAAUGAGAGUAUAGCUGUUAUUUGUUACUUGGUCAUAAAGGUAUUUGGAAAAGCACUGAUCUUAGAAUUUUAAUAAAAGGCAUUUAUUACCAAAAAAAAAAAAACACUGGAUAUAUUGACCUUAAAAUGAGUAAUUAGUAUUUUCCAGUAAAGCAUUUUGGAUUCAACAUAGACUAUGCUUCACCCUACCUCACUUCUAUUAGAAAACCUUUUUUAAAAAGAAAUUUUCUUUUUGUCAGCUUUAGUAAAUAAUGUCAUUCAGGAUUCCUAUUCACAAUCUGAGAUCUGCCACUUAACUUGCUCAGAAGCCUUACAGUCCACACCAUUUGUUCUAUCCUUUCAAUUCAGGUUUUAUUUGUUUAUUUAUUUAUUUAUUUUUUUUGGCGUGCUGUUGCACAAUCUUGGCUCACUGCAACCUCUGCCUUCUGGGUUCAAGUGAUUCUCCUGCCUCAGCCUCCCGAGUAGCUAAGGUUACAGGCGUGCGCUAUCACGCCCAGCUAAUUUUUGUAUUUUUAGUAGAGAUGGGGUUUCACCAUGUUAGCCAGGCUGGUGUUGAACUCCUGACCUCAAGUGAUCCACCCGCCUCGGCCUCCCAAAGUGCUGGGAUUACAGGUGUGAGCCACUGCACCUGGCCUCAAUUCAGUUUUUAACUUGAGCUUAAACGAGAUAUUUUUUAAAAGUUAAAAUCUGUGUUGAGGCAUAUCAAGAAUUGCUAUGUCUCUUGGGGGAGAGAUGUGAAUUCCAUCAACAUAGAUAUGCUAGUUUAUAGUGAACUGUUAGGAAUGCUGUACCCUUGACUCAUACUUAGUCUUUUCUUUGUGGCUUGUGGCUCUCUUUUCAACUUCAUUAACAUGUAAUUGAAGUGUACUAAAUGCAUAUACUUAUUUUUUAUGUUUUUUCAAUUUUUUAUUUUUUGUGUGUGUUGGGGGGUCUCACUAUGUUGCCCAGGCUAGUCUUGAACUCCUGGCCUAAAGUGAUGCUCCCACCUUGGCAUCCCAAAGCACUUUACAGAUGUGAGGCACUGCACUUUAAAUGUGUAUAUUUAAAAAUGUACAGUUUGGUUAGUUUUGACAUGAGCAUAUGCCUGUGAAAUCAUCAUUCCCAAGAGAGCAAACACUUCUGUUCCCCCAAAAGGUUCUUGUGCCUCUCUGUUUUGUGUCCUUUCUUCUCCUCCCAUCUUCAGGAAACCACUGAUGGGGUUUUUGUCACUAUAAUUAGUUUACAUUUUCUAGAAUUUUUCUGGAAGUGGAAUCAUAGAUAUAUACUUCUUUUUUAAUCUGACUUCUUUCACUUAGCAUAAUAAUUUUGAGAUUCACGCAUGUUGUUGCCUGUGUAACAGUUGGUUACUUUUUAUUGCCAAGUAGCAUUUCAUUGGAUGGAUAGAUCAUCAUUUGUUUAUUCAUUGAUCAGUUGAUUGACAUUUGGGUUUCAGUUUUUGGCUCUUAAAAAUAAAGCUUGAUAGUACAUUUGUAUAGAAAUCUUUGUGUGGGCAUAAAUUUUCAUUUCUCUUAACCAAAUACCUAGAAGUAGAGUGGCUAGGUGGAGUGGUAGCUGUGUAAUGUUUUAAGAAAACUAUAUUUUUAAAAGUUUGUACAAUUUUACAUUCCUCUCAGCAGUGUGUAGAGCUGUUCCACAUCCUCACCAACACUAGAUGUGGUCAUUCUUUCUCAUAUUAGCCAUUCUAGUGGAAAUAUAGUGGCAUAUCAGUGUGAUUUUAGUUUGCAUUUCCCUGAUGAUUAAUAAUGUUGAACAUCUUUUCAUGGGUUUAUUGCCCAUUUCUAGAAGUUAUUUUACAUCUCAGCCAUUUCCUCACUGAGCUGUCUUAUUCUUAAAUUGUAAGAGUUCUUUAGAUAUUGUGGAUACAAGUACUUUUUCUAAUGUAUGUGUUGCAAGUAAGUGUUUUCUUUGUGGUUUGCUUUUUUGUUUUCAUAAGGGUUAUCUUUUGAAGAACUGUUUUUUUGUUUUUUUUAUUACUUUGAAGCCCAGUUUACUAAUUUUUUCUUUUUUGUUUUUUUUUGAGAUGGAGUUUUGCUCUUGUUGCCCAGGCUGGAGUGCAAUGGCGCGAUCUCGGCUCACAGCAACUUCGCCUCCCAGGUUCAGGCCAUUCUCCUGCCUCAGCCUCCAGAGUAGCUAGGAUUACAGGCAUGCGCCACCACGCCCGGCUAAUUUUGUAUUUUUAGUAGAGACGGGUUUCUCCAUGUUGGUCAGGCUGGUCUGGAACUCCGGACCUCAGGUGAUCCACCCGCCUUGGCCUCCCAAAGUGCUGGGAUUAUAGGCGUGAGCCACCGCACCCGGCCUAAUUUUUUCUUUUAUAAAUCAUGCUUCCUUGUGUUUUGAGAAAUUGCCUAGCCUAAGUUCAGGAAGAUAUUCUCCCAUCUUUUAAGAUUUUUAUAUGAAGCAUAUAUGGUUUUGCAUUUAGGCCUAGGACCCGUUUUGAAUUAAUUUUUGUGUAUUAUGUAAAGUGUCAGUGUUGGCUUUUCUCCCCACCUGGAUAUCCAGUUGAUCCACUUUGUUUGUUGAAAGACUUUUUUCCUCCAGUGAUUUGUCUUUACAACUUUGCCAAAAAUCAGUUAACCAAACGGGUAGGUCUUUCUGAACUCUUCUUUUCUGUUUUAUUGAUCUGUCUCUUUACACCAAUCCCAAAAGGCCUUGACUACUGUUGUUUUAUAGUAAAUCUUGAAAUCAGGGUAAAUCUUUCAACUUUGUUCUUUUAAAAAGUUGCUCUGCUUAUUCUAGGUCUUUACUAUCAGCUUGCCGAUUUCUGCCACAAAGCCUGCUGCAAUUUUGAUUGGGAUUGCAUUGAAUAUACAAACCCUUUGGAAAGAAUGGCAUUUUCACAGUAUUUAAUCUUUCAACCCAUGAACUUAGUAUCUUAGUACCAUUUAUUUAGGUCUUCUUUAAGUUUUCUUCGCAAUAUUUUGUAGUUCUAAGUGUAGAGGCCUUGUAUAUGUUUUUUUGUGUGUUUGUUUGAGACGGAGUUUCACUCUUGUUGCCCAGGCUGGGCCUCCCGGGUUCAAGCGAUUUUCAUGCCUCAGCCUCCCAAGUAGCUGGAAUUACGGGCAUGUGCCACCAUGCCUGGCUGAUUUUGUAUUUUUAGUGGUCAGGCUGGUCUCGAACUCCUGUCCUCAGGUGACUCACCCGCCUUGGCUUCCCAAAGUGCUGAGGUUACAGGCGUGAGGCACCGCGCCCAGCCUGUCUUUUGUUAAAUUUACAUUUAGAAAUUUUACAUAUUUUGAUGCUACUGUAAAACAGUUGUUUUUCUUAAUUCCACUUUCCAAUUUUUUGCUUGCUAGUAUUUAAGAAUUCAGUUCAUUUUAAUACAUUAACCUUUUAUCCUGCAGUUUUGUUAAAUUCACUUAUUGAAUAUAGUUAUUGUUUUCUAGAUUCUCUGGGAUUUUCUAUAUAAAUAGUGAUAUCUGUAAAUAAGGAGAGCUUUAUUUUUACUUUCCAAUCUUCAUGCCUAUUUUUUGCUUGUUGUUUUUCUUGUCUUAUUACUUUAUUGAGUAAUCUCCAUAUCAGUGUUGCACAGAAGUGGUAAAAGCAGAUAUCCUUGUCUUCUUCCUGAUCUCAGGCUGAGAAAUUCAGUCUUUAACCGUUAACUGUGAUGUUAGAUGUAGGUUGUUCAUGGAUCCCCUAUAUCUGUUUGUAGAAGUUUCCUACUAAUUCUAAUUUGCUGAGAGGCAUUUUUUUUUGUUUUUUUUUUUUUUUGAGACAGAGUCUCGCUUUGUCACCCGGGCUGGAGUGCAGUGGCAUGAUCUCGGCUCACUGCAAGCUCUGCCUCCCGGGUUCACGCCAUUCUCCUGCCUCAGCUUCCCGAGUAGCUGGGACUGCAGGCACCGGCCACCACGCCUGGCUAAUUUUUUGUAUUUUUAGGAGAGACGGGGUUUCACCGUGUUAGCCAGGAUGGUCUCGACCUCCUGACCUCGUGAACCGCCCGUCCCAAAGUGCUGGGAUUACAGGCGUGAGCCACCACACCCGGCCUGGUUUUUUUUAAUCAUGAUUGGAUGUUGCGUUUUUGUCAGAAGCUUUUAAAAAAAUAUCUGUUCACAUGAUCAUAUGGGCUUUCUGCUUUAUUCUGCUAAUAUAGUAUAUUACAUUUUCUGAAUGGUUUAAUCUUGCCAUUUCUAGGAUAAACUAUUUGGUUAUAUUUUAGUAUCCUUUUUAUAUAAUAUUGAUGUUCAAUUUUUAAUUUUUGUGAAUGAUUUUUGUAUCUGUAUUCUUUAGGGAUCUUGUUCUAUUAUUUUUUGUAACGUCUGUGAGGUUUUGGUAUUAUAGUUGUAUGACCUAAAAAAGUGAAGUGGGUAGUGAUCUCCUUUUUUUUUGUUUGUAAAACUUUUCAUAAUUUUUGUAUUAUUUCUUCUUUGAAAGAAUUCACCAGUGAAACAGACUAUGGCUUUCUUUUGGGGGAAGUUUUUUGUUUUUUUUUUUUUUCUUUUGAGACGGAGUCUUGCUCCGUCGCCAGGCUGGAGUGCAGUGCUGCGAUCUCGGCUCACUGCAACCUCCGCCUCUUGGGUUCAAGUGAUUCUCCUGCCUCAGCCUCCUGAGCAGCUGGGACUACAGGCGCGUGCUACCACACCCAGCUAAUUAUUGUAUUUUUAGUAGAGACGUUGGCCAGGAUGGUCUCGAUCUCCUGACCUCGUGAUCCCAAAGUGCUGGGAUUACAGGCAUGAGCCACCGCGCCUGGCCGGGGAAGGUUUUUAAUGAUAAAAUCAGCUUCUUUAAUAAAUAUAAGAGUAUUCACAUUCUCGUAUCAAUUUUAGUAAGCUUUAUUUUCCAAGAAAUUUGUUUCUUUUAUCUACACUGUCAAAUUUAUUGGCAUAAGGCUUUUUACUAUUUCUUAUUUUUUAAAUGUUUGUAGGAUUGAUGGGGAUGCCCCUUAUUUCUACGAUUUUUUUUUCUCUCUGUAUCUAGCUCGAGGUUUGUAAAUUUUUUUUUUCAAAGAACCAAAGUUUGAUUUUGUAAUUUUCUCUAUUGUCUGCAUUUUUAUUCAUCCUGCCAUAUCACUGUAAUUUCCUUUCUUCUACUUACUGUUGGUUUACAUUUCUUUUUCCAAGUUUUUUUCUGUUAUUGUUUAGAUUACUAACAUUUAAUGUAAUUAUCGGUUGUUGGAAUUAGACCUGCCAUCUUCCUAUUACUGGUUUUGUUUGUCCUUUCUGUUUUUUUUUCUUUCUUUCUUCUGUUUCUUUUUUCUUGACAUCUUUGGAUUUUUAACAUUCCAUUUUCAUUUGCCUCUUGACUUUUUGGCUAUGUCUUUUUCUGUGUGUUGUGUGUGUGUGUGUGUGUGUGUGUGUGUGUGUGUGUGUUGUGUAAUUGCUCCAGGUAGUAAAUAUAUUUACUUAACCUUUUAUUAUCAGCUUAGAGUUAAUAUUUUAUCACUUCACAUAGAAUGUAGAAGGCUUGCAGCCAUAAAAGUCCCUUUACCCUCCCCCCAGAGACAUUUAUGUUACAGUUGUCAUAUGUGUUAUAUUUAUGUUGAAACCCUACUACACAGUGUUACAGUAUUUGCUUUCAACAGUCUACAUAUUUUAAAGACCCUAAUAGGAAAAAUAAAUUUAUAUUUACUCAGAUGUUUGCCAUUUCUUUUGCUCUGCUUUCAUUCUUAAAGAUCUCAGCUUCUCUCUAAAAUUUUCAUUUGAUUCUUUUUAAACUAGUUUUUCUUUCUCUGCUGAUAACUUGUAUCUUUCCAUGCAUUUGUGUUUGUGUUUGCCUCAUGGAAAGUAGGUGUAAUGGCUGUUCUACAGUCUUUGUGUGAUAAUCUCAACAUUUUCAUUGUCUUGGAGUUGGCAUCUGUUGAUUGCAAUUUUUUUUUUUUAAGAAUUUGUCAGAUUUUCCUACUUCUUUGUAUGUCCAGUAGUUUUGGAUUAUAUCCUGGACAUUGUGAGUUUCAUGUUGUAUAGAUGUUGUGUGCUGUUGUAAUCCUCUGCAGAAUGCUGUUUGUUUCAGUAGGUAUCUAACUUGGUUAGAUCUGCCUUGGUUAUAUACCAGACUAUAAAUUCUCUAUGCUGUCUGUGGACAGGGGUUCCUUUCUCAGUUCAGUUUUCAAGACCAGUGAGUGCUGUGCUUCUUUGAGCCUGCCGUGCAUAUCCAUAUCUCAGGUGUGAGCCUAAGACAAGCGGGAGUUAAUUCACACAAUGGCAGGUCCCAUUUCUACCUUCUUUCCUCUCUGGUUUUCCCCACACUUUACAGCCCACAGGUGCCUUUUUCAUUAGUUCCUUUAACCACAAAGACCGUGUUUCUGUUGGAGUUUUAGUCUCUGCACCUGUGCUUCACUGCAUAGCUCCCUGACUGGGGCCCACCUGUGGGGCAGAGUUGUAGAGAAAAGACAAAAAAGAAAGUUUUUACUCCAUGGAAAGGAAACUUUUUAGAAACUUUUUACUCACCUCCCAAAUCUGCCUGCUUUUGUCUACUUCUUAUUGUCCUCAAGUAUUAUAGUUACAUUUUGUGUUCUGUCUGCUAUAGCAGAAGCAGAACUCUGGUUUGUGACAUUUUAUUUUAUUUUUAUUUUUGAGACUGAGUCUUGCUCUUGCUGCCCAGGCUGGAGUGCUGUGGCAGGAUCUCGGUUCACUGUAACCUCUGCCUCCUGGGUUCAAGCGAUUCUUGAGCCUCACCCUCCUGAGUAGCUGGGAUUACGAGUGCCCACCACCACGCCCAUCUAAUUUUUGUAUUUUUAUUAGAGACAGGGUUUUAUCAUGUUGGCCAGGCUGGUCACGAACUCCUGACCUCAAGUGAUCCGCCUGCCUUGGCCUCGCAAAGUGCUGGGAUUCCAGGUGGGAGCCACCGUGCCUGACCAGGUUUUGUGACAUUAUUUAAUGUGUUGGAUAUGUGAUUAUUCUUUUUCAACAUGGUAGCCUUUUUUUGUUUUUGUUUUUGAGACGGAGUCUUGCUCCGUCUCCCAGGCUGGAGUGCGGUGGCACGAUCUAGGCUCACUGCAAGCUCUGCCUCCCAGGUUCACGCCAUUCUCCUGCCUCAGCCUCCCGAGUAGCUGGGACUACAGGCGCCCGCCACCACGCCUGGCUAAUUUUUUUUGGUAUUUUUAGUAGAGACGGGGUUUCACCAUGUUAGCCAGGAUGGUCUCAAUCUGCUGACCUCAUGAUCUGCUUGCCUCGGCCUCCCAGAGUGCUGGGAUUACAGGCGUGAGCACCACUCCCGGUCUCAACAUGGUAGCCUUUUACAAAUUACUAUAUUUUUUUCAAAUUGUAGUAAUUCAUACAGCAAGCAUAUAUAAUGGUAGGACAAAACACCUUAAGCCAAGAUGUCAUCUCCAUGGUCUGUCCAGGUAGCAUAGAACACAAAAGGAGAUGUGAUUGAAAGAUGUUGCUUCAUCUACAUGUUUCUACUAUUGUCUGGGGUUCCUUAGGAGCCAAGGAGAACCUCGCUGUGAUUGGCAUUGGAAAGACCUGUGGUUGGAAGAAAAUUACCUGGGAACAUUCCAGCCUCAUCUUUUUUUUUUUUUUUUUUUUUUUUGAGACGGAGUCUUGCUCUGUCACCCAAGCUGGAGUGCAGUGGCGCUAUCUCGGCUCACUGCAACCUCCGGCUCUCGGGUUCAAGCAAUUCUCCUGCCUCAGCCUCCUGAGUAGCUGGGACUACAGGCAUGUGCCACCACACCGGGCUAAUUUUUUGUUUGGUGGAGACGGGGUUUUACCGUGUUAGCCAGGAUGGUCUCCAUCUCUUGACCUCGUGAUCCACCCGCCUUGGCCUCCCAAAGUGCUGGAAUUACAGGCGUGAGCCACCGCCCCUGGCCCAGCCUCAUCUUUAAGCCAUAAUUUGGCUAUUGUGUUAGUGAAUAAACCUGAAAGGUACAUCUUCAUUCAUACAUAAACAUAAUUUAGUUUUCAUUAGGUAGAUUCCUUGUUCACAUCCAGCUGAGAACAUGACACUAAAGAAAUCGGGCUUUAAUUGGGGAGGGAAAGAGAGAGAACGUGGAGUCCCUUUGGUUGUCACUUAAGAGAUACAGAUGAAGGAGAAGUAGAGUUGGAGGUCAGAAGGGCCAGAAGGUAAAUGUAGUCUAAUAUUAGUCAUAGUGAGGUGAAGGCUUUUGGAGGGUAGAGAUUCACCUAGGGUGAGAAUUAUUUCCUAAGUUCUAGAGUAGCAUGGUAAAUAACAAAUAGUCUUAGGUGCUUUGUCAGGAACUGAUAAUGACUACAAGUAUAUUUGAAAUCAUAAGAGUUAUAUUUAUGUUUGCUGUGAUCCUCUCAUAGUAGCUGUGAAAUAUUUAAAGUAAGGCAUAAAAUUAUUAUAUCUAUAUCUAUAUCUAUAAGUAAAAAUGGUCUAUUUUAAUGCCUUCAGUAUCAUAGUUGAGUAUUAAGCUAAUGCUAACUUCAUAAAAUCAUUUUUUCCUAAGAUAAUUUUUGAGAUUUAUAGGAAGGUAGAAAUGCAUGCAUUUCCUCUGGAUUUGCCAUUUGUUGCAUAGUAUUAUGUAUAACAUUUUCUUAAACAAAAAGCUUAAAGAAAAUAUUAGCAAAUCAAACCUAGCUGUGUAGUGAAAGAAUAACAUGCAUAUAUGAAUUGGUCUAUUGUACAAAUUCUAGGAUAAUUCAGUAUUUGCAAAUAUGUCACUAUAAUUCAGAAUGUAAGUAAAGGAGAAAUUCAUUAUCUCACUAGAUGCUUAAAGAAAGCUUCUGAAAAAAAUUUAGCCAUUUCUUAAUAAAAUUAUAAAAAAUAGGAAUAGAAGGAAACUACAUAAAUAUGGUAAAUAAUCUUUACUAAAAUACAACAACAAACCAACCUAUUAAAAUAUGAAAUACCAAAACUGUCACUGUGAAAGUCACAGGCAAUACAAAAAUUAUUGCUAUCACAACUAUUUUGUAUAGCUUAGUAUUAUUGCUUUGGGCUAGUAAUGUAAGGCUAAAUUCUUUAUUUCCAGAAAAUAUAGGUCUAGGAAAUCUAAAGAGAUUCAUAUGUGAGACUAUUAGCACUAAUAAGAAAGUAUGGUAAAGUAGCUGGAUACAAAGAAGAGAAAUCAAUAACCUCUUUAUUUUGCAACACAGUAAAAAAAUGGAAGUAAAACUGAAUGAACAGAAUGUAUUCUCAUAUAUAUUAAAUAUCUGUUUUACUAUGCAUUUAAAAUCCAGAGCUUACCAUUUUUGGGAAACUCUACAAAAAGAUAUAUGACAUGUUGAUUCCAAAAGGAUUUUAUGAGGACUAAGUGAGAUAAAACACACUAAAAUGUUCAAGAGAAUUAUCAAGGUUGCCUAUACAAUAUAUUGAAUGAGAAAUUGUCGAGGAAAAGAAAGGCAGCUGCAAUUUCUAAAGGGAAUCUACAGUGAGAAGUAGUCUGAUUCACAAACCUCUGGUUAAAUAUGGUGUCUUGACUACACUUGUUUUCUCCUUCCCUAAAGUCUGCAAUAAUCUCAAAGGAAGCUUAAAAAUGUUAAUUCAUAGCUGGGCAGAUGGGGUGUUGUCACCUGUAAUCCCAGCUACUUCGGAGGCAGAGGCAGGAGAAUUGCUUGAACCCAGGAGGUGGAGGUUGCAGUGAGCCAAGAUUGCACCACUGCACUCCAGCCUGGGGACGGAGUGAGACUCUGUCUCAAUAAAUAAAUAAAAUAAUAAAAUACAUAAAUAAGUGAAAUCUUAAUUCAUAAGGAGAAACAUAACAGUAAAGGAGACAGUGACCAAAGAUUUUAACAAUUUUUCAAAACAGAAAGUGAAUGGAGGGAGUAGUAACUGAGUUCACAGAGAAAGAUACCACCUAAGUACCUGCAGAGGUCAGUUAUGGAGAUAACAGCAUGCCCCAGGGAUAUCUUGAGAGAGUUCCUUGUGCUUGGGGGCUCCACGUAUUCCAAAAGGCUGAAGUCAGUUUUACAGCUCACAGUGGAAAUUCCUUAAAAGUCCAUAUCCAGAUCUCUUAGACCUUCCUCUCCUACACUCCAGCAGAUGGGUAACUACUUCAGUCCCGUCUGCUGGGGAAAUGGGAGGAGCGCUAGAACCGGAAGUGCUCCAGACUAGAGAGGUGAAGCACGGGAUUGAAAGUCAAGUGAGCCUGUACAGGUCUGCACACUGAAGUGUAGGGCCCUACCUCCUUCCUUCUUCACUCCUCCUCAAGGCAGCACUUAGAUGAGUUGAUCCCUUCACACCCCACCCAGCAGUUCGUUCUACCUGGCAAAACUUAACAGCUUCGGUGAAGAAACCUCCACAUUACUGAACAUUUGGAGGUGUCCCAAUGAAAAGGCGUCGAUUAGCAAGGUAAAAGUAACAGAACCAUGGCUCAGUUUCCAACACCUUUUGGUGGCAGCCUGGAUAUCUGGGCCAUAACUGUAGAGGAAAGAGCGAAGCAUGAUCAGCAGUUCCAUAGUUUAAAGCCAAUAUCUGGAUUCAUUACUGGUGAUCAAGCUAGAAACUUUUUUUUUCAAUCUGGGUUACCUCAACCUGUUUUAGCACAGAUAUGGGCACUAGCUGACAUGAAUAAUGAUGGAAGAAUGGAUCAAGUGGAGUUUUCCAUAGCUAUGAAACUUAUCAAACUGAAGCUACAAGGAUAUCAGCUACCCUCUGCACUUCCCCCUGUCAUGAAACAGCAACCAGUUGCUAUUUCUAGCGCACCAGCAUUUGCAGCUGUGCCCCCCCUGGCUAACGGGGCUCCCCCUGUUAUACAACCUCUGCCUGCAUUUGCUCAUCCUGCAGCCACAUUGCCAAAGAGUUCUUCCUUUAGUAGAUCUGGUCCAGGGUCACAACUAAACACUAAAUUACAAAAGGCACAGUCAUUUGAUGUGGCCAGUGUCCCACCAGUGGCAGAGUGGGCUGUUCCUCAGUCAUCAAGACUGAAAUACAGGCAAUUAUUCAAUAGUCAUGACAAAACUAUGAGUGGACACUUAACAGGUCCCCAAGCAAGAACUAUUCUUAUGCAGUCAAGUUUACCACAGGCUCAGCUGGCUUCAAUAUGGAAUCUUUCUGACAUUGAUCAAGAUGGAAAACUUACAGCAGAGGAAUUUAUCCUGGCAAUGCACCUCAUUGAUGUAGCUAUGUCUGGCCAACCACUGCCACCUGUCCUGCCUCCAGAAUACAUUCCACCUUCUUUUAGAAGAGUUCGAUCUGGCAGUGGUAUAUCUGUCAUAAGCUCAACAUCUGUAGAUCAGAGGCUACCAGAGGAACCAGUUUUAGAAGAUGAACAACAACAAUUAGAAAAGAAAUUACCUGUAACGUUUGAAGAUAAGAAGCGGGAGAACUUUGAACGUGGCAACCUGGAACUGGAGAAACGAAGGCAAGCUCUCCUGGAACAGCAGCGCAAGGAGCAGGAGCGCCUGGCCCAGCUGGAGCGGGCGGAGCAGGAGAGGAAGGAGCGUGAGCGCCAGGAGCAAGAGCGCAAAAGACAACUGGAACUGGAGAAGCAACUGGAAAAGCAGCGGGAGCUAGAACGGCAGAGAGAGGAGGAGAGGAGGAAAGAAAUUGAGAGGCGAGAGGCUGCAAAACGGGAACUUGAAAGGCAACGACAACUUGAGUGGGAACGGAAUCGAAGGCAAGAACUACUAAAUCAAAGAAACAAAGAACAAGAGGACAUAGUUGUACUGAAAGCAAAGAAAAAGACUUUGGAAUUUGAAUUAGAAGCUCUAAAUGAUAAAAAGCAUCAACUAGAAGGGAAACUUCAAGAUAUCAGAUGUCGAUUGACCACCCAAAGGCAAGAAAUUGAGAGCACAAACAAAUCUAGAGAGUUGAGAAUUGCCGAAAUCACCCAUCUACAGCAACAAUUACAGGAAUCUCAGCAAAUGCUUGGAAGACUUAUUCCAGAAAAACAGAUACUCAAUGACCAAUUAAAACAAGUUCAGCAGAACAGUUUGCACAGAGAUUCACUUGUUACACUUAAAAGAGCCUUAGAAGCAAAAGAACUAGCUCGGCAGCACCUACGAGACCAACUGGAUGAAGUGGAGAAAGAAACUAGAUCAAAACUACAGGAGAUUGAUAUUUUCAAUAAUCAGCUGAAGGAACUAAGAGAAAUACACAAUAAGCAACAACUCCAGAAGCAAAAGUCCAUGGAGGCUGAACGACUGAAACAGAAAGAACAAGAACGAAAGAUCAUAGAAUUAGAAAAACAAAAAGAAGAAGCCCAAAGACGAGCUCAGGAAAGGGACAAGCAGUGGCUGGAGCAUGUGCAGCAGGAGGACGAGCAUCAGAGACCAAGAAAACUCCACGAAGAGGAAAAACUGAAAAGGGAGGAGAGUGUCAAAAAGAAGGAUGGCGAGGAAAAAGGCAAACAGGAAGCACAAGACAAGCUGGGUCGGCUUUUCCAUCAACACCAAGAACCAGCUAAGCCAGCUGUCCAGGCACCCUGGUCCACUGCAGAAAAAGGUCCACUUACCAUUUCUGCACAGGAAAAUGUAAAAGUGGUGUAUUACCGGGCACUGUACCCCUUUGAAUCCAGAAGCCAUGAUGAAAUCACUAUCCAGCCAGGAGACAUAGUCAUGGUGGAUGAAAGCCAAACUGGAGAACCCGGCUGGCUUGGAGGAGAAUUAAAAGGAAAGACAGGGUGGUUCCCUGCAAACUAUGCAGAGAAAAUCCCAGAAAAUGAGGUUCCCGCUCCAGUGAAACCAGUGACUGAUUCAACAUCUGCCCCUGCCCCCAAACUGGCCUUGCGUGAGACCCCCGCCCCUUUGGCAGUAACCUCUUCAGAGCCCUCCACGACCCCUAAUAACUGGGCCGACUUCAGCUCCACGUGGCCCACCAGCACGAAUGAGAAACCAGAAACGGAUAACUGGGAUGCAUGGGCAGCCCAGCCCUCUCUCACCGUUCCAAGUGCCGGCCAGUUAAGGCAGAGGUCCGCCUUUACUCCAGCCACGGCCACUGGCUCCUCCCCGUCUCCUGUGCUAGGCCAGGGUGAAAAGGUGGAGGGGCUACAAGCUCAAGCCCUAUAUCCUUGGAGAGCCAAAAAAGACAACCACUUAAAUUUUAACAAAAAUGAUGUCAUCACCGUCCUGGAACAGCAAGACAUGUGGUGGUUUGGAGAAGUUCAAGGUCAGAAGGGUUGGUUCCCCAAGUCUUACGUGAAACUCAUUUCAGGGCCCAUAAGGAAGUCUACAAGCAUGGAUUCUGGUUCUUCAGAGAGUCCUGCUAGUCUAAAGCGAGUAGCCUCUCCAGCAGCCAAGCCGGUCGUUUCGGGAGAAGAAUUUAUUGCCAUGUACACUUACGAGAGUUCUGAGCAAGGAGAUUUAACCUUUCAGCAAGGGGAUGUGAUUUUGGUUACCAAGAAAGAUGGUGACUGGUGGACAGGAACAGUGGGCGACAAGGCCGGAGUCUUCCCUUCUAACUAUGUGAGGCUUAAAGAUUCAGAGGGCUCUGGAACUGCUGGGAAAACAGGGAGUUUAGGAAAAAAACCUGAAAUUGCCCAGGUUAUUGCCUCAUACACCGCCACCGGCCCCGAGCAGCUCACUCUCGCCCCUGGUCAGCUGAUUUUGAUCCGAAAAAAGAACCCAGGUGGAUGGUGGGAAGGAGAGCUGCAAGCACGUGGGAAAAAGCGCCAGAUAGGCUGGUUCCCAGCUAAUUAUGUAAAGCUUCUAAGCCCUGGGACGAGCAAAAUCACUCCAACAGAGCCACCUAAGUCAACAGCAUUAGCGGCAGUGUGCCAGGUGAUUGGGAUGUACGACUACACCGCGCAGAAUGACGAUGAGCUGGCCUUCAACAAGGGCCAGAUCAUCAACGUCCUCAACAAGGAGGACCCUGACUGGUGGAAAGGAGAAGUCAAUGGACAAGUGGGGCUCUUCCCAUCCAAUUAUGUGAAGCUGACCACAGACAUGGACCCAAGCCAGCAAUGGUGUUCAGACUUACAUCUCUUGGAUAUGUUGACCCCAACUGAAAGAAAGCGACAAGGAUACAUCCACGAGCUCAUUGUCACCGAGGAGAACUAUGUGAAUGACCUGCAGCUGGUCACAGAGAUUUUUCAAAAACCCCUGAUGGAGUCUGAGCUGCUGACAGAAAAAGAGGUUGCUAUGAUUUUUGUGAACUGGAAGGAGCUGAUUAUGUGUAAUAUCAAACUACUAAAAGCGCUGAGAGUCCGCAAGAAGAUGUCCGGGGAGAAGAUGCCUGUGAAGAUGAUUGGAGACAUCCUGAGCGCACAGCUGCCGCACAUGCAGCCCUACAUCCGCUUCUGCAGCCGCCAGCUCAACGGGGCUGCCCUGAUCCAGCAGAAGACGGAUGAGGCCCCAGACUUCAAGGAGUUCGUCAAAAGAUUGGCAAUGGAUCCUCGGUGUAAAGGGAUGCCACUCUCUAGUUUUAUACUGAAGCCUAUGCAACGGGUAACAAGAUACCCACUGAUCAUUAAAAAUAUCCUGGAAAACACCCCUGAAAACCACCCGGACCACAGCCACUUGAAGCACGCCCUGGAGAAGGCGGAAGAGCUCUGUUCCCAGGUGAACGAAGGGGUGCGGGAGAAGGAGAACUCUGACCGGCUGGAGUGGAUCCAGGCCCACGUGCAGUGUGAAGGCCUGUCUGAGCAACUUGUGUUCAAUUCAGUGACCAAUUGCUUGGGGCCGCGCAAAUUUCUGCACAGUGGGAAGCUCUACAAGGCCAAGAGCAACAAGGAGCUGUAUGGCUUCCUUUUCAACGACUUCCUCCUGCUGACUCAGAUCACGAAGCCUUUGGGGUCUUCUGGCACCGACAAAGUCUUCAGCCCCAAAUCAAACCUGCAGUAUAAAAUGUAUAAAACACCUAUUUUCCUAAAUGAGGUUCUAGUAAAAUUACCCACCGACCCUUCUGGAGACGAGCCCAUCUUCCACAUCUCCCACAUUGACCGCGUCUAUACUCUCCGAGCAGAAAGCAUAAAUGAAAGGACUGCCUGGGUGCAGAAAAUCAAAGCUGCUUCUGAACUCUACAUAGAGACUGAGAAAAAGAAGCGCGAGAAAGCGUACCUGGUCCGUUCCCAAAGGGCAACAGGCAUUGGAAGGUUGAUGGUGAACGUGGUUGAAGGCAUCGAGUUGAAACCCUGUCGGUCACAUGGAAAGAGCAACCCGUACUGUGAGGUGACCAUGGGUUCCCAGUGCCACAUCACCAAGACGAUCCAGGACACUCUGAACCCCAAGUGGAAUUCCAACUGCCAGUUCUUCAUCCGAGACCUGGAGCAGGAAGUCCUCUGCAUCACUGUGUUCGAGAGGGACCAGUUCUCACCAGAUGAUUUUUUGGGUCGGACGGAGAUCCGUGUGGCGGACAUCAAGAAAGACCAGGGCUCCAAAGGUCCAGUUACGAAGUGUCUUCUGCUGCACGAAGUCCCCACGGGAGAGAUUGUGGUCCGCUUGGACCUGCAGUUGUUUGAUGAGCCGUAGGCAGCGGGCUCAGGGUGUGCUCAGCAGGGUCCCAGCCCACGGCCACACAUGCUGUCUGGAAAUUGUAUUCCUUUUCUAAGAAACCACCAUUUGGUAUUCAGUCACAGGGAUAUGGGAUGGCAAAGACAGGCCCCUCAAAGCUCCUAGGAAUCAUUCUCGACAAUCCUCCCUGCCCCGAAACAAUUUCCUGUUUCAUGAAACAAAGCUGUGUUUUCCUUUGUCCUCACUACAGGUCUCAUUAUGGCUUCUAGGGUCGCUGAAAUCCCAUAGCCCUCAACAGGGUGCAGCUGGGAGUCUAGCCCCUUCCCGGGCUUGAGGGAUGGGUCUGGUUACUAUAAAAUAGAUUUAUAAAUGCAAUGUCUAUAUUUUUGGAGAACUCAUGUAACCCUCCUGUUUCUUACAUCCACCAGUCCCCAAGUAGACUUCUUGGCCUACAAUGCCCAGUCCUUGGUGUGAGUUUAGAAACAAUUAUGACGGUCCUGUCAUUGCUUCAGAAUCCCAUCUCUCCUGCAGGGAAAUGCUGCCUAGAGCUGAUCACUCGGUGAGACGGUCUGAUCAGGCCCUGGCUUAGCUCUUUGAAGAGCUGGUCUAUGGAAGUUUCCAGCAUGUGCACCGUUAUAGCCGUUCCUUCCCCCUCUAGGCCUUGUAUUAAUAUAUGUCAAUGAAAACACACUGGUGUAUUGUUGCGUGGAUUCAGUUCUGAUUCCCAGCAUGCUUAGAAUAUGGUCACAGAAAGUCAUUAUCUAGAAAGUCACCCCUCUGCUGGAUCAGAUCACUACAGGUCACUGGAAAGGCAACUUUACAAUGUUGGGUCACUGGGUCUCGGUUGGCAGCCAUGUUGGAAAAAUCUCUUUUGGCUCGGAGGCCUGUGAUAUUUCAUAGCAGCAGUCGUUGCUGGUGACCUGUUCUGUGCUUGAAUGUGCUGAAUCCUGAUUGUUGUAGGACAUUUCAACAGCUCUUUUUGGUACGUUCCCCAAAAAGCCAUGUCCUAGAUCCCCAAGGCGUGAAAAGGAAAAAUAUCAAGCUGGAGGUUGGGAAAGAAAAUGAAGGCAGUCCAUUAUGUGGUGGGUGAAAGACCCUAGGAGGAUGCAAGCCCCGCACAUCCCGGGGCAAAGACCUAAGACACUUUUCCACCCUCCACCACCCCAACCUCACAUAAUAUGCUUGUUGCAAGAGUCAGGACUUUAUGACUAUGUGCCAAGCUGUUUGGUUUGAGUUCUUUAAUUUUUUUUUCCCUUAAAUGCCAGGAGAUCAUCUGGUUAGUUAGAUAGUAACUUGAUUUGCUAAUGAAAAGUGGGGGCCGUGUUUUGUUUGCAUGUUAAUAUUCUCAUAAUCCUAGUUUGUUGUGGUCAUGAAAUGUCCUUUGCAUGUUCUGUUGGUACUGGAGUCUAGCUUUCCUGUACUAGAUGGUGUUCUCUUUGAUUGUAGGUCCUUAGACUUUAAUUAGGGUUAUCAAAGUGCUUUCUAAAUGAUAGCAUCAGCGUUGUGGCAGAGUACCUCCUUUGCUGGGAACUGAAUGUGUAGUGUUAUCAUUUCCCAUGAGAGCCCGGUCAUACUUCAAGCAAUUUUUUUAAAAGUGUGUGUUGGAAAGGACAACAAAGUUUACAUUUCAUACUUUUAAGAAAUACUUUAUUAUUUAUUUAUUGAAGAUAGUGUAGAAUUUUGUAUCAAGAACAACAGACAUAAGUAUUUUUUGAAACAAGCAAAUAUACCCUGUAGUUAGAAACUUUCAACUGAACAUGUUAGAGACCAAGUUUAACUUCAGGCAUGCAUUUGUUUACCAUUUCCCAGCAGAAAACAUGGUUAAAAUACUUUAAGUUUAUAUUUUUUGAUGUUGUUAAGAAACUUUUAAAUUAAAUCUAUAAAUAGACAUGCAACUCAUGCUUUCCUAUUUCUAUAACCAACACCGUUUGUUUAGUGUAUUUAUGAAAGAUAUGCUACCAUGGUAGAAAGAAAAGUAUUCAAUGUGUAAAUGGGGUAGUGUGGGUCACCAUUCCGAUCUCUUUUUGUUUUCUGUCCUGUCUUUUCUUCAUUGACUUUAUUUGCGUGUUAAUGUUGGACAUCAUUGUUCAUGUAGGUAGCGUAUGGUAUGCACAAUGACAAACAAUCGUUUUAGGUCCCAGGUCACCCACUCAUAGUGUCCUAUUAUUGGAAUUAAUGUAGCAUGAGAAAGCAAUAUGUGACUCUUUUUCCUCAAGUGACUCUGUUGAGCAUCCUUGAGAUGCUCCUGCCAUGUAGCAAGUUCUGGAUUAGUGUCCUUGUAUUUACUGGUGUAAUUUGUAAUGUAACCAAUUGUCCGUAUGGAGGAGUCGGGCUGGCCCUCGGACCCAGCUGUGAUUCAUGAGUUGUGUCACAGGGAUUGAGAAACAUGGGUGAUGCAUGGAGUCUCAAACCAUUGGGCCUCUCUGUUCCUUCACCUCUACCUUCUUGACCACCUGGGCUAUAUUUCAUAGAAAUUAAAUGCUCCUUGCCAACAAGGAGUCUGUCUCCUAGCUCUUUGUUUUCUAAAUAUAGGAGUUCUCUAGGCCACUGCAUCCCGGCAUCCUGAUCCCAGCCUUUUAGACACCCCUGCAAGCGUUCCUCUGCUCUGAGCCACACUGCUAGCUUCUCCUGCACACUCUGAUCUCCUUUAGCCCAAGAAGGGGCUGUGCUGGUCAUAGGGUUAUGCUGUAACCCUCAGUCUUCCCUGAGAACUGAACUAUCCUGGGACCUCUUGGGCUGAGCCUUCUUCACAGAGCAGUUCUCUAGAAGGCAGAGUCCACAUCCUGGUCCCUCUGGGGCAGGGCCUGUCUGGCUGCUGGCAUCACCCUGGCAGGUGGAUGGACAGCAUCAUCUCCUGGAACCAGGUUUGCUGUGACCAUGAGAGCCUGAAGAUGUGGCUCAUUCGGAUCCAGGCCUGGACUAAUCUGGAAAGAGGGACUUUCUAGGUGCAGGUCACCAGGGAUGCUUGAGAAACUAGAGCCAGACUUCCUUGUUUGUUUGGAUAAUAUGUCCCUGUCCUCUGAUAGCAGAGGAAAGAGCUCUGCUCCCAAAGAACAUUCAUGUAAGAGGAGGCAUUUUUUUCUUCUUUGCUUUUUUUAAACAACCUAAAGUAUGACCUAAGUGUAUGAAACUAACUGAUUUCUUUGGGUAGAGUAGCCCUGAAUUUAACUGGGGAAAAAAUCCCAUCAGACUAUGAGUAAAUUGACCACCCACAUUAAGUCUUAUCUCGGUGACCUGGUACCAAAGCCCAGGUGUCCUCCAGGGGAGUAUUCUGGGGUGGCAGGGGGAUUAGGUGCUAGCGCCAGCAGGGAAGGACACUUGCAGGUCUGCCUUCCAAGGCUAAGCAGGCCGGCUGUCUCUCCAGGAACUGGCUAGGACAAGUGUAAAGCCACUGACCACACAGAACCAGGAUGUUCUAGAAUCUGAUGGGGCUGAAGAUGAAGGGAGAAAUGGACAAGGCACUUCUGGCUUUAUUGAAAAGGUGAAGCUCUUGGAGUAUAUUUUAGAGUAGGCCAGUACCUUGUAUAAGCAGAAAAAGACUUCUCUAUCUCCACUCCAAGUCGUUUUUUUCUAGUUGAUUGGGCCUUUUUGAUUGAUAAGAAGAAAAUGUGUUUUGUACGUGUAACAACUUUAAGAAUUUCCAUUGGAAACAAAGUAUGAUUUGAUUUGAUUUGAUUUCUAAGUUCUCCCUUCCUUUUCAAGGUUAGCGAUGUGCUUUAUAGCAGACACUAGCACUUUUACAUGAAUACCUGGUGUGCUUUGGAUGUAACAGGGUCAUUUUGGGCUCGAGGUGAGUGUGCAAUUAGCAGCAGGUCUGCUUGGUCCAGAUAUGCUUGUUUACAAGUUUAGAGCAUCCUAUGCCAGAAAGUGAGAUGAAAACAAAGGCACCUGGAUUGCUUUGUUUUGCUUUUAGAUAAAAGAGCUUUAGCUCACACCAGGCAGAAGCAUAACCAGUAGCCCCAGAAACCGGUAGCAUGAUGAAGCCCUCAGACAGUAUAGUCUGAGCCACCAUAAGAGGCAUUAGGGAAAACUAACACCUCCUUCUUUUUGCACCGUGGGGUGCUGAAAUUCCUGCUAGAGACUUCCCCUUACUUCCAUGAAUGGCCCAGGGGCUGCUUAGUAUAUCAUUAGAAUGUUCAUUCUCCUCCUUUUCCCUGGAGUGGACCAGUGAGACCAAAUGCUUGUGUUUCUCUAUGUUUUCAGUUCAUUUGUUCAAAUGACCCAGAAGAUGAAUCCAUUUCUGGGAAGGCUGAGCUCAGAUGAGGAUUGCUAGGCCAGCCUAGGUUCUGGGGCGGAUCUCAGGGACAGAAACAGGCUUGUAUUAAGUAUGAGUGGCAGGUACUUCUCUAGAACAGCCCUAACCUGCACUAGUGAGGGGGGCUCAGGAAUUCCCAUGACAUUGAUCUAGCAGCCUCCUGCACGUAGACACUCAGUUCAUUUUAGGGACGUUCAAUGCUUGAUCAAAUGGGGGGCAUUUUCUUUCUUUCUUUUUUUCCCCAGCUACAGUGUAAUUGCCUACCUGCCUGGGCCCCUUCUAGAGGAAGGUGGGCUUUCCUUGUCCGUCAGGCUGCACUCAUGAGGUGAUAUCGUAAAGCAGCAGAAAGACUGAGGGUGCAAAGAAACCACAGCUGCCAUUCACGGGGCAGCUCCCUCUAGCUCUUCUGCCCAGUGACCUUACAGGCUUUAGAGGAGCCUGAUGAGAGCUAUCCUGGGGGCCAAGGGAUGCAUUCCCUGCAGCUUCCUCCUGGGGGACCCACAGGUCAGCCCAUUCCAGGAGAAGCAGUCUUAGGCCCGUUUGCAUCCCCUGCCACUGCCAUGUGCCUGCCAGCCCGGUUUCUGAUGAAGACGUGGCUCAGUCCCUGCUCUCCUUGUCGCAGUGGCUUGUACUUCAUGUGCAGUAGCCCAGGGCCCGCCUUCUAGAGUGAAUGUUUCCCUCGAGCCCUUGGAUAUUUUUAUUCUAUUUUGAAUGGUUCCGAUCAAUUAAUGUUGCUUUGUGUGGGGUUCUUCAGAGAAAUAAUGCAAACCGGCCAGGUGCGGUGGCUCACACCUGUAAUCCCAACACUUUGAGGGGCUGAGGCAGGUGGAUCACCUGAGGUCAGGAGUUCGAGAACAGCCUGGCCAACGUGGCGAAACCUUGUCUCUACUAAAAAUACAAAAAUUAGCCAGGGGUGGUGGCAGGCACCUGUAAUCCCAGCUACUCAGGAGGCUGAGGCAGGAGAAUCACUCGAACCUGGGAGGCGGAGGUUGCAGUGAGCCGAGAUCACGCCACUGCACUCCAGCCUGGGUAACAGAGCGAGAGUCCUUCUCAAAACAAACAAAAAAAGAGCUAAUGCAGACCUCUUCUGGUUAGACCUGACACGGAGGAAGUAAUUGGCUGGUCAACUUAAUGGCGCCCCACAGCUUCCUCUGGAUCCUGCUUCUUUGUACUUGGAACACAGUUUAUUUGAGCUAGAGGAAAGGAAAGUUCUAGAAUUCCUGUUUCCUCAGCCUGCACUGUAUCAGAUCCAGGAUAUGUCUGCAUUUCAUCAGGAUCAAGUAAGAUACAUAACCUUAUAUCUGUAGGAGCCAGAAAAAAAAAAAUCUAUUCCUGAUAGGCAUGGAAACUUAGUCCACAUGAAAGACAGAAGACAUCUAACAGCUGUCUGUCUUGGGAGCAUUAAAACCCAGACACCAAGACACACUAGACAGUCCAUCUCUGGGUUGUGAUCUCUCAGAAACAUCUUAGUAGUUAAUGCACUGUUCAUUUAGGGAGUCCCCAUCCUGGUCCAGGCCACCCUCCUAGAAGCUGGGCGGCAGCUGGACGGGCCUGCCUUGGUGGCAUUCAAGCAAGCCUAAUUGGAUUAGGUUGGUGCAAAAGUGAUUGCGGUUUUUGCCAUUGCUUUUGAUGGCAAACUAACUUUAAGUCAUUAAAAUAAGACCCAACGCUUAUAAAAGAGUUCAUAUCCACCUCCCAAUAACUUCUUUAGUUCCAUGCAGCCUCAAUCAGUUCCUCCAUUCAAAGGAACCCUCUUUACCCUGGCCCUGGGGGAGCCAUAUUACACCCACAUCAUAAUUUUUCUGACACUAUGUGUGCUUGUCAAAUUUCAGGGUCAGUUUCCCCUUAUUGGAUGUCAGGGGUGUUUUGUGAGUUGUGUUUUAAUAGGAUUCUGUUCGAUUUUCUAUACCAGCCUAUAUUGUUACUAUCAUCUGCCUAGUAUGAAUAUUUUAGUAUUCAAAGCCCACCAGAUAAAGCUGUGUUCAGAAGUGGACUUUUUGGUCAGCCUUGAAAAAAAAAAAAUCAGCAUUUCUCUGAUAUUUCCUGAGGAUUAACCAGAAACUAAGGUUUCUUUUUAGGCAGUGGUAAGAAUGCGUAUUUUCUUCUUCCAGAAGUUCUGGUUUUAUACUUUUAUCUUUUGAAAGAAUAACAUUCCUGUGCGACUCUGCUUCUCUUCGCUUUUGCAUUUCUCUUUUUUAACUCAAAUCUCUUAUUUCCUGCCGUUCCUGUAUCUAAACAGAAUGGGGGCCUCAGGCAGACAGGAACCAAAGAAAGGGUGUAGUGGCUUUGCAGCGUUGGGUGAGCAGCAGCCGCUGCCAUUCUGUGCACUGUCACCGGCGGGGGUGGAGGGUCUCCCUGUAGGAGGAGGAAACUCGCUGUUUUCACUGGCAGAUUUCAAGGUGCCGGCUCCACCUACCGCAGCUGCUAGGCAUUGCUCUUGUGUAGAUCGCAGAAGGAGUUAUUGGUGAUGUGGGGUGUAGGGGAAGACAGGAAAACGGACUCAGAGCUAGGAAUGUGGGCCUGGCAGAGACCGAAGGCUGGGUGGGAAGGAAGCUCGCGGCGAGCCUAGGGUUCAAGCCUAGCGCGCCAGGGGUCUCCAGUGAGACCUUGCUCUUCCCUGCCGCUGAGGCUGGGGCUGCACGGAGGUCCUCAGGCUUCCCACCCUUUCUGCAUCAGCUUUAGUGUCUGUCGGCUGGGUGGACUGCAGGGCAGGUGACCUGGAGGAGGCCCUGCUCCCCAGCAAGCGUUCUAGGAGUUACGGUGUGCUCUAUUGGGAUUGGAUUACAGUCUCUACUUGUAGACUUUGACUUCUGGAAUUUUAGGUGGAAGGGAAUUUUUGUUGGUGGGACGCAGCAGCUCAGUGCGUGGUGUGUGCAUGCGUGUUUGUGCGUGCGUGUGCAUGUAUGUGUUUGUGCGUGCACGUGUGCGUGUGUGUGCAUGGGUUUGCGUGCAUGCAUGUGUGUGCGUGCGCGUGUUUGUGUGUGCAUGUGUGUGUGUCUACGUGUGUGUGCACGCAUGUGUGUGCGUGUAUGUGUGCGUGUGUGCAUGUUUGUGAGUGCAUGUGUUUGUGCGUGUGUGCGUAUUUGUGUGUGUGCGUGUGUGUGCGUGUGUAUGUGCGUGUAUGCAUGUGCAUGUUUGUGUGUGCGUGCAUAUGUGUAUGUGUGUGCGCGUGCGUGUGCGUGCAUGUGUGCGCAUGCGUGUGUACCUACCCACACCUAGGGGGAUGCAUGGCUCUGUGCCUUGGAGAGGGAAACAGGAAAUACGUUGCUCCACAGUCCUGUCAUCCUGGUCAGGACUAGUCGCGUGGUUUGCGGACAGAGUGCAAAAUGAAAAUGCGAGGCCCCUUGUUCAGGUGAUGAAGCAUUUCUAGACAGUGAGAGGAGAGCAUUAAGCCAAGCUCAGGUCCCUUCUGAGUGCAUAGCCCCUUGUGGCUGCCAGGCAGCACACCCAGGAGGCCGGCCCUGACCACACUGUUCUCUGCUGGUUCCCGAAGCUGAUGGGCUCUGUCUUAGGUCUUCUUACUUUGAAAGGUCUCCCGGCAGGCUGUGGCAAGCUGCGCGGAUACACUUUUCUAAACGUCUGCAUUUAUUUCCUAAAAGCACAAAUGGCCUGGACUAGCUAGUGGGUGUGGAACCGAGCCCCUAGUUCACAGCUGUACCCCAAGGCUGGAGAGGGGGUUGCCGGUGGUGGCAGGAGCUCUGGGCUCCCAGUUCAGGAUGGGCCACAGGGCGUCAAGCAGCUGUGAGCCUUUACCAUUGAGCUCACUGCUUGGAAAUAAAACCCUUCCUCUGGGCCUUGGGCAUCCACUGGGAGCUUUUCUCCCCUUUCCUGGGAGGACAGCAAGCCUUUUCCAACCUUCUGCCUUCAAAGAGAAGCAGGGUCAUAGAAGUGCUCAGUGUCCCUUCCCCAGUGGCUGGACACUUGCUCCUCCAGCCUUCACCCCCUGGAGAGAAGGGGAGUCUGCGGAGCCAGUGCCUCCCUGCCCAGCUGGGCCACACGAUCUGGUCUGCGGGUGUCUGGGAGGAACCUGCUUCGGAGAGGCUGCGACCUCCCAGCUAGACUCUCCCCUUAGGAUCCCAUGUAUGGGGAUGGUAGGAGAGAAAAGAUCCCUCUGUGUAAGUAGCCUCAAGUUCUAGAAGACCAUGGCCCCGGGAGGCAGCUGACCAUGAAGCUGGGCUUCCUGUUGUUGCUUUCUUUCACGAGCUUUUACUUUUCCUGGGCUGGACGCUCCAAAAUGUUUGCAGUUCCAUUUGCUUUUUGCAAGUAGGUCCCCAUCUCCAUAUACAUUGAGCAAUAAUCCUCACUAUGUUUCCUGAUUCUGUCUGGGAUUAUAUUUGCUAAGUAAAAAUGUUGACAGAAAUUGCAAACUCAUCUCACCUGGAUUUGAUUGAGUCACCUUGAAUGACAUAACAAAUUAUGGCUUUGUUUUCAUGCGUCAUGCAAUCUUCCGGACUACGGGAAGUUCUGCAAGUGUUCUCCAGGGGCAUUUCAUUAAUAGCGUGUCAGCAUUAGUUUUAAUGAAUGAACAUUUGAGGUACAUUCUAUAAAUCAAUAUCCUUAAAAUGUCAUCUGCUAAACAUUCACUGUGACAGAAAGUAGAUAUUUUAGCAAGAUCUAUGUUAAUGCUACUUAAUUUUAGACAUGCAUUUAAAGCCUACAUGGCCAAUAGCCCAAGUAUCUUUGAACUGUGAAAUCAACCUCAGAUCUCAUCUGCUGUAGCCCCGCAAGCCGGAGUCUGUGCCCUCCAUGACCCUUCUUAUCCCUUGGUGGCCCUGCAUAGAUAGGGGAGUUGGCCCCUGCCCACCCCGUGUUGUAUUGCCUUAGCUCCAUCAGCUUUGUACCCUCACACGUAUAGGUGGUGAACUUAUGUGUAAAUACAUGUGUACAGAUGAGAAACUGCAACAAAAAUGUCCUGUGGAUGAUAAUCAGCUCAGUUUCCGGUUUUCUACAUUCUGUGCUGUUUCCAGCUAAGAAAAAGGCGAACUCCCACUAUAUAAAGGGAAAAGGUUGUAUUCAUUUCAUGUUCCUCAUGAAAUCUCUGCUGUAUGUUUAUGGAAUGGCCAUGACUAAAUGUAUAUAUGGUAUGUAAGAGGCCAUGCUGUUAAAUGUUGCAUAAACUAACACAGAUUCUGUAGUCAAAAAUAUUUAACUUGUUAUUGUAAAAUGUGAUUUGUCAUUGAGAGAUUAUUUUUCUGUAUGUAUAUGAGAGUAUUUUAGGAAUCUAAUUUAAGUGCAUAAAACUAUAGAAAAAAAUUUAAAACCUAUUCCAAGAGUAGAAAAUGCUUAAUGAGAUUACUUGGGUUCAACUCAACUAAAUUUCUUAUAUUAAAAAAAAAUUCCAAGUUGUAUAUGUUAGAAAUCAAAUGAGUCAUUUUUUUUCCUGCAGGAAAUAUGAUAAAUUUCAGUGUAAUGGAUGGUGGCGUGAUCAAAUGAAAAGUAUCCUGUAGCUAUGACCUCGCAUGGGACCUUGGUGUUGCAUUAAAAAUGGAUUUUUGCAGAUCACAUAUCUGAGAGGGUACUUGUGUCAGGAAGGAUGAGAGGAUAGGGAGCCUGUUUUUCAUCAGAUCCAUGUGCCACGCAGGCUUCCUUGGGUUCUAGUGGAUUUGUUAGGGAUCUGGGGCUGACGCAGCUAUCCCACUAGAGAGGCCACUCUCUGACUUCCAGGUCGCCCUUUCUACUUCUGUAUCUGGAUUGAUUCAGUUUAUCCCUAAUUAGCGUUUGCGUUUUCCAUGAAAUUUCCUGAUGCAUCCUCACUGUCUUCAACUGUUGCAUAGCCAGGUGGGUGGAUGGAUGGUUUAGGGUUUCUGAGUUAAGCCGUUUUGGGGCAGGCUUCUGGAUGCCCAUGUUUCCAUGGAGACCCCAGGGGGAAGAUGCCUUCCUCCCGUCUGCAUUCCCAGAAAAGGAUCAGAAGUCCAGGCUGCUUCUGGGGCACAGACUUUCUGUACUUGGCCACCAGAAGUGCCCCUUAGGCCACCUAAGGAGGAUUCUGUGAAACUCAAUGUCUAAACCCCUGAGAAAGGCAUUCAGAAAUGAUUUCAGGAGGGGGCAACCCCAGGAGUCCAGCCUCCCCUGGCAGCCUGGAAAUACUGCAGUAACAAAAAGAGCUGGUUUCUGGUGAUCUGAAUGCAUUGUGUUUGGGGGUGACACCGCUGGUGGAAGGUUGAGGGCCUGUGGUCUGAAAAGACAUCUGAAGAAUGUGUUAGGUUUUCAACAUUUCUUUGAACAGGCUGCGUGCAUCUUAAUGCUGUCAACCAGCAACUGGAGCCCCUUUUUUGAGAGGCCCGAACCAGUAAAGCUGCUGACUUCAGGAGUAUGGGAAGCUGUGAUUUCUGGAAGCUUCCUGGAAUCUAUUUAGGUGCAUGAAUAAUCUGCAAAUCACUUAGAGGCACUGUCCAUGUGGUCCAUAACUGGCUUUAUUCCCAAAGAUGGAGCUGUUCAGAGAUUUCUUUGUUCAGGCGCAGCCUUGGAAGGCCACCUAAGGCCUGCCAGCAGAGGAGAUGAGCUCUGGUCUACCAACCCCAAACAGGCCCUGACUCUCCUUCCUUAGAACGAUGCCCUCUGGCUGGGGUGGCAAGAGGGCUGUGAGUGGAAACAAGUCAGCCAGUCAACUGUCCCUUGGGCCUUGGUUGUUUCAAAAAAGUCUGGGGACAAGAAAAGCUAGAACAUGGGGCCCUCCCUUCCCAGGAGUGCUAGCGAACCCUCCCAGAUAGCCUUUGCCUGUUUGGAAAAGAAUGUAAUCCAUCAGAACGUGAGCUCCUUGUGCUUCCAGUGACAAGCGGGCCACAGUGCUGGUGGCAUGUUGCUUCCCUCACAGCCCUGCCCAGGGGUAGGACCAGGCCCGCCCCUUGAUGGAUGUGCUGUUGAUUGUAAUAUACUUCUGUUGCCAAAUAAUGGUACUGUUUAAUUUUCCAUAAAAGAGAGACUAUAUUGUCUGAUAUGUAAUGUUAAUGGAAUUCUAAGAAUUACUAGACACUAUUAUAAAUUGUAGACUUACGUAUUUGUCUAAAGGUUUGAUGAAGCAGGGCCAAAACAUUGUUUCUUCUUUUUUGUUUGAAAGAAGCUGAGGUUUGUUUUUGCUGUUUGAGUGUUCCUUUGGCAACUUAUUAUGUGUGAAAUGUUAAAUUUUACCGAUUAAGAUGAUGGUAACUGAGACCUUUCUUUAAACCAGUAGCAACAUCAGUACAAAUUGCUCUUCCUGUGUAUCUUGAACCUAAAAAGAACAAUCUCUUCAAAAACAAAAACAAAAACAAAAAACAACUCUUUGGUCAUUUUGACCUGUGUGGUUUAAAUUCAAAUAGUUCAUGAAUAAAAGGAGAAAAGCCAA